ACACUUGAAGAAAUUUAUUGUUUCGUUGAGCAUUAUUACAGAUCAGCAUUGUCAAGAACCAAUGGUGUUCCCUGAAGAAAGAAUACAACAUGGGACACAGGACUCUCAGAAAGAUUUCUUCAUUUCAGUAAUUGGCACAUCUUUGAAGCAGCUGUCCAGUGGUUCUUGGAGCCUCACUGCUAAACCGUCAGUAAGAAAAAUACUGACUCUGCAAAACCAAAUACAUCUGGAAUCCGAAUCCUCUUGCAAAACUCUGAGCAGUGAUAUCCAACCUUUCUGGCACCCAGAGACCACCGGACCUCCUUUUCUACAAUCAAGCCAAACCAGUUCCUGUUGUUGGUGCCAAGAUAGACUACAGCUGGAAAUUCCCCAAAUGACCAACAGAUCACCUGGUGCCAACUGACUGACCACCAGGAAGAGCGACUAUUGACUUUGGGCUUAAAAGUCAUCUAAUCCACACUGUUUCUCACUCCCCUGACUACCCUCCUCUGCCCUGAGGUUUUUUUGCCUUUAUAAUCUCCUAUUCACUG